GACAGCCCCGCACACCCACUGGGGUGGAGAAGGGGGCCAGCGGGCUGCGGGAAUUCAGCCUCCGGCGGGGGCUGCCACCGAGGGGAAUUUCCCCUCUUUGAAAAGGCUGGGGACCCCUCCACCCCACCCUUUCACUGGGCUUCUUAAAGAGAUCACACCGUUUUCCCUUGGACUUCUUGGAAGGCAGACUUGGGACGCUUUGUGGGGACUUUGAACCUUUCCUUCCUGCUUUCUUUCCAGCAGGCAGCCUUGCUCUGGCUGGUGGAGUCGGGGCUCCCGGGCAUGGCACUGACUAGCCGACCCGGUGCUGACUUGGCGCCGGGGCUCUUUCAGCCUCUGCUGGCAUCCUGCUUCCCCCCUCCUGGGGUGCAGUGGUGAGUCUGGGGGCCUGCCCCCGAGGGCACUGGAGGAGUGUUGCAGGCAUCACCCACGCCCUCUGCACCCACGCUGGAGGACGGGGAGGUUGUCAGGGGCUAUGAUGAGAUGAGUGGGGGCCGCUUCGACUUUGAUGAUGGAGGGGCGUACUGCGGGGGCUGGGAGGGGGGAAAGGCCCAUGGGCAUGGACUGUGCACAGGCCCCAAGGGCCAGGGCGAAUACUCUGGCUCCUGGAACUUUGGCUUUGAGGUGGCAGGUGUCUACACCUGGCCCAGCGGAAACACCUUUGAGGGAUACUGGAGCCAGGGCAAACGGCAUGGGCUGGGCAUAGAGACCAAGGGGCGCUGGCUCUACAAGGGCGAGUGGACACAUGGCUUCAAGGGACGCUACGGAAUCCGGCAGAGCUCAAGCAGCGGUGCCAAGUAUGAGGGCACCUGGAACAAUGGCCUGCAAGACGGCUAUGGCACCGAGACCUAUGCUGAUGGAGUCAAAUGCUACAAAGGAAACAGCAGUCUUCCAAACUGGAGAGGACAACGCAUUAGUGGAUGGUGAAGUCAAUUCAGUGGGUCACGACCUGCAUUUUUCAAAAGGAAAGAACAGAACAGAAUAGAAAAGUAUCGGAGUAUUUCACAGAGAAUAAGAUAAAGUAUUAUUUUCUGAAAGAUUUAUUCAGUUGGCGAGAUACACAUAUAUAUGCACACACACAAUGUGUGAGAGUUCGUGUGUGUUUAAAAGUGUCUGCAUGUAUGUGUGUUUUGCAAUGUAAAGUGUGUUUCUUACUGCAAGUCAUGGUCCAAAAAGUUUGACACUCAUUGUUCUAAGGUGACUUGACUUGGCGUCUUCUUCAAAGCCCUGUCAUUCCCAUCUCGCCGACCCCUCCCUGUCCUCUAGGCUUUCUCUUUGGUCUGAGGAUAAGCUCUCCAGCUCUCGCAUGGGAAGGGGAAGGUGGGGCUGGUGCAGGAGCUCUGGCCUCCCAAACCCUGUUGUAAGCUGCUUGGCACCCCUCCCCCUCCUAUAGCCCUCAUUCCUCCCCUGGCCAUAUAUAGCAAAGCUAAAAACAGCUGCUGACUUAAAGCAUCCGCACAUGCCCCAGCCCUGAAAGAGUUAUGUGCCUGUUGCGUGGCUGGCUGGCUGUUCCCACCGAGACACUCGCGGACUCUGGACCUCCUAGAGUCCUUAGUGCUUGUUAUUUUCUGAGGUUCUUGGUCCUGGGGCCCCUGCGUUGGCCUCAGAGACCCAUAAAUACCCUGAAACUUCAGGCGUGAUGUGAACAUACGUGCAAGACUAUCUGUGUUUUUCUGGGAGGCAUUUUCUCACAUAGUCUCAGAUUCUCCAAGUCAUCUCUGGCUCAAAUAAGUUCCAGAACCACUGAUGACUUUAUUAAUCCCACCCCAAAAUGUGCACUGGAAGAAUCAAGCCCAAAGUUGACUUUUUUCCAUAAAGCUAAUAAAAAUAAUAACAGUAAGGCCAAGGUGGGCAGAUUGCUGGAGCCAGGAGUUCAAGACCAGCCUGGGCAACAUGGUGAAACCCCAUCUCUACAAAAAAGAAAAAUACAAAAAUUAGCUGGACAUGGUGGCACAUGCCUAUAGUCCCAACUACUUGAGAGGCUAAGGUGGGAGGAUCGCUUGAGCCCGGGAGGUCGAGGCUGCAGUGAGCCAUGAUCACGCUACUGCACUCCAGGCUAUGCAACAGAAUGAGACACUGUGUCAAAAAAAAAUAAAAUAAAUAUAAUAAUAAUAAAGAUAGUUAAUAUUUUUGGAGUGCUUACUAAGUCCCAGGCACCAUUCCUAGCACUUGAGGUACUUGAGGUAUGUUAUGUUACUUAUUUAUUUAUUUUUUGAGACGGAAUUCCGCUCUUGUCACCCAGGCUGGGGUACAAUGGCGCAAUCUUGGCUCACUGUAACCUCUGCCUCCUGGAUUCAAGCAAUUCUCCUGCCUCAGCCUCCUCAGUAGCUGUGACUACAGGCAUGUGCCACCAUGCCCAGCUAACUUUUUGUUUUAGUAGAGACGGGAUUUCACCAUUUUGGCCAGGCUAGUCUUGAGCUCCUGACCUCAGGUGAUCCCCCUGCCUUGGCCUCCCAAAGUGCUGGGAUUACAGGGGUGAGCCACUGCACCCAGCCUGUUGUAUUGUUUAAACCUUCACACAACAACCUCAUGGAGAAGUAGUUACGGCUCCUGUUUUACAUAUGAGGAAACUGACAUGGAGAUCAUGCAAGUACCUCACUCAAGGUCGUCCAGCUAAUAAGAAGCAGAGAUGCAAUUUGAUAAUAAUAAGUGAUCAUUAAACAUUUUGUAAUAUAAAUAAGUAUUUUAAAUAAUAAAUGGUAAACAAUGAUACAGACUAGGACAUGCUUCAUAAUUCGUGAGACCCAGUGCAAAAUGAAAAUGUGGACCCCUUCUUUAAAAUCAUUAAGAAUUUUAAGAUGGGGACAACAGAGCAUUAACCCAGACGCAGGGCCCUUCUGAGUGCUGGGUCCUACGAGACUGCAUGGUUCCAGCACCCAUGAAGCUGGCCUUGACAAUAGUAAUAACUGUGCCUGGCUACUAGUUAAUAUGCCUUUACUAUGUACCAGACUCCGGCUAAAAGUCUUAUGGGCACUGUAUCACUUGGGUUACCUCAUAACCCUCUCAUCUACUACCCUAGUGGCUUGUAAACUGUUAUAAUUGCAAUCCCACUAUAAGAUAUGUGUUUUAUUCCUUCCCUGGCAGUGAAUGCAAAAAAAUAUGUAUUUUACAUUGUAAUUCUAUACCUAUACACAUCUAAAAAGAAUGUAAAAUUGAAACAAACCGUCAUGGAACAAGAUUUCCCUUCCUAGGUGCAAUGCUUGCUAUUUUCUCUUUUAUUCUAUUUUGUUGAGAGAAUUAAAUGAGGCCCUGAUCCAUGUAAAGCUCUUAGAACAGGGUAUGGCAUGUGUUAGUGCUUUUAUUACUACUACUACUACUAUUAUUGUUACAUGCUGAAAAGUUGAGACUUUAUGUUUAAUUAUGACGAUUGGGUCAAAAACCCAAGCUUCUGCGCUCUGGAUCCAGUUUUCUUUCUUCUGCUCAAAGCUUAUGACUUCAGCUAAUUUUAGUCCAAUUGACUCUGAACACGGGAGUUACGUGAUUUUGCCAGGCUGGAGGACUGAGCAGUAAGUACCUGGUAUCACAUUCUCUGGGCCUGUGAUACAUGUUCCUUGCAGAGAUAAGCUUGAAGGAACUUAACUUCCAUAUUUAUUUAUUUAUUUGCAUAAUAGAAUAUCUUUUCUGUUGAUCAGUUUGUCUAUCUUUAUGCCAAUGUCAUGCUGCCUUGGUUACUGUAGCUUUAUAUUGUCAUAAAAUCAGAGUAAAUUCUUCAACUUUGCUCUUCCUGUUCAAAAUUGGAUUAUUCUGGAUCAUUUCCAUUUUAAAACCAGCUUCUUCAGCCUGGGCAACAGAGUGAGACCCUGUCUCAAAAACAAAAACAAAACAAAACAAACAAAGAAAAGAAAACCAGCCUCUUGAUUUCUGAAAAAGGCCUGCUGGGAUUUUGAUGAAGACUGUAUUAAAUCUAUAGAUCAGUUUGAGAGAAUGGACAUCUUAUUAGCAGUGAGGCUUCCAACCCGUGAACAUGGUAUAUAUCCCUAUUUGUUUAGGUUUUCUUUAAUUUCACGCAGCAAUGUUUUAGAGAAUUCAAUGUCUUACACAUCUUUUGUUAAUUUUAUCCCUAGAUAUUUUAUUUUCUGUGCUAUUGUAAACGGCAUUUAACAUUUUAUUUUUUCAAUUGUUCACUGCUAGUUUAUAGAAAUACAACUAUUUUUGUAUAUUGACUUUGAAUUCUUUUACCUUGCUCAGUUAAUUUCUUAGUUCUAGUGGAUCUUUUUGUUUUUGUUUUUCAGGUGAAAAGGAAUCUCUUUUAACUUAAAAUAGUUUGACUGUUAUUGAAAAUCAAGUGUAGAGGCCCUGAGAGAAUCUGAUAUUACUAAAGGAAGACAUGUGAUAUUUAAGCAACUGAGACUUAGAGUAGGCAGAUCUGGGUUCAAAUCCCAGCUGUGCCGGUUCUUAACCAUAUGAACCUGGGUGCACCAUGUAACCUCCCUGAGCUUCUGUUUCCUUUUUUCCUUUAGGGAUGUGUUAAAAUCGCCCUCAGAAUAUGGUCGAGACAAUGAAACAAGACAAUGAAGCACUGAGCAUCAUGCCUGGCACAUAGGAAAUGCCAAAAUAUAUAUUCCCGUAUUUCCUUCACAUUCCAAAGGGUGAAUUAAUUCAGGAUGGCCUGAACCAUAGCUGUCACUGUCUUCGGGAGGAUAUUUGAGGACAAAAACGAGUUUUUGACUUUGGAACAGUAAAUAAGACAAGACUUUGAUUCGCUUAGUUCUGCCUUGAGUCCUGCCAGUGUAGAUGGAAUCCAUGCCAGACAUGAUUCCAUUUCGAAUGUAGAAUCAGCAUAAUUUAACCUCAUCUUGGAAAUCUCAUGUCCCAGUUCACAGCCAGGCAUCAGCGUGACAGUCAGCUGAGCUGCUGUCUUGGCAGCUUCUGGGCAUUCUAUGGAGACCCCAGGAGAGCACAGCAGACCCUUAGCAGAACAGAAAAGCGGACCGUAUUAGUCUUUCCUGUCCACGGCCUUGUUUUCAGUGAUUCAUGUGCCCGAUUGGCCAAAUCUCUGCAGACGUGCCCCUGUCCGAGGCCAGGCUUCUGGGAUUCAUCGAGCUUGCUUGUUUCCGGGACCUGCUAAUUCCGUGCCCAGCAGCUGUUCCCCGGAGCAGGCCCUGCCCUCCACACCCUCAUGAGGAAUGCCGAGUCUCAUUUUCUGAGGGCCCUGGUUGAGGGUGGGGUGUGGGGCGAGGGGGACAGGGUUGCUUCCUGCCAUAGACUUCCUGCCUUGGAGGGUUAUCCUUGUUCUCACCUAUCCCUUCCCGAGCUGAAGCCACAGAGUAGGAGAGAAGUUAGGGCUGGCACACCUCCCUCCCGUGUAACUUUCACUCCCUGCUUAAAGGGAACUGAUGAGAGUUGCCUGGCACAGAUCUGUGCCUGGCAGAAUCCACAGAGCAGCCCAGGUGUGCUAGGAACUCCAGAGUGACCCCUGCUCCAGGCCAGGAAUGAGCACCUUGUGCCUGGAGGUCUUCCUGCCACUGCUGGCUGCCCAUUGCUGUGGAUGGGGUAGAGCUGGAGUCACACAUGGAGGCUGGACAGCUGCAUGCAGCCUGCAGGGGACACUCUGGAUGGCAUGUACCAUGUUUUUAUUAUUUCUAUUUUUAAUUAAAUUGGAAUCCUUUAUGGAUACCUUUUUUUUCUUUUUCUUUUUUUUAACAGGGUCUUGCUCUGUCACCCAGGCUGGAGUGCAAUGGUACAAUCACGGCUCACUGCAGCCUCGACCUCCUGGGCUCAAGUGAUCCUCCCACCCCAGCCUGCAAGUACCUAGGAUUACAGGCACACAUCACCAUGCCUGGCUAAUUUUUUUGUAGAGACGGGGUUUCUCCAUGUUGCCCUGGCUGGUCUCAAACUUCUGAGCCCGAGCCAUCCUCCUGCCUCAGCUUCCCAAAUUGCUGGGAUUAUAGGCAUGAGUCACUGUGCCCGGCCUAUGGCUACCUUUUAACAAAGUGAUCAAAUUUAACAUCAUCAGUGACAGACAAACCUACAGUAUGUACCCUUGAUGGGAUGUACAGAGAAGGCCAGCGCUUUAAGAGGCCAAGGCAGGAGGAUUGCUUGAGCCCAGGAGUUCAAGACCAGCCUGGGCAACACAGUGAGACCCUAUCUCUAAAAAAAAAAAAAAAAAAAAAAGACAGAUAGGAUCUGACCCAUUUGAUGAGAUUCUUUUAGCUCUUGUGUUGAGAAAAGGCUGUUUUGGGAAAAUAGGUAUUAGGUGAGGGGAGGUGGCAUGGAGACCUGGUAGUGAGUUUAUUACAUUAUGACUGGUGAGAAGAUGGUGGUUUGCACCACUACCUUGUAGUAGCAGAGGUGGUGAGAAGACACAUUUUGAAGCAAAACUUAUAGACUGGAUAGGAUUGAGAGAAAGAGGAGUUAAAGAUGGUCCCAAGGCUUUUGCCUGAACCAUGGAAGGAUGGUGUUGCCAUGAACUGAGAUGGGGUGAGGGUUUGAGGAGGAAGGGUCAGGAGUUCAGUACUGGACACCAUGGGUGAGAGAUGCCUGUUGGAAGUGUCCAUGGGCAUUGGGUUUCUGGGCAGGCCUGUGCACAGGUAGGUGGGUCUCCUUUUAGACCCUCUCCCCUUGACCUUUCUUGCCUUCUGCACACACAAUCAUUUCUGCUCUCCAAGGCCCUUAGGGUUGCUGAGCUGACCCAAGGCCUGGAAAUGGGCCUUUUCCCCAGGCCACAGGCUCCAGGGCUGUCAGCACCCAGGAGAUGCCUCCUGGUUAAUCCCCUGCUUCUGGGGGUGAGCCACGGGGCAUCAUCUGGGGCAGCAGCCUCUGGAUGUAGGGGUGGUGGAGCCUUGCGGGCUCAGGGACUUGUCAUCCACCCGCUGCAACCUGACCCUGCUCCUGGGAGCUGGUCCCAAAUGCCGCCAGCUCCUCCGCUUCGGGUUGUCUGUUGGUGAUCCCAGGAAACCAGAGACUAUGGAGAUUUGAUGGACAGCGGCAUUUGGAAGCCAUGGGAAGGGACUUUGGUGCCAGCCUUGCAGGCGAGCCAGAGAGCAAGGCCUUGGGAUUGUUACGGGAAAAAUGUAACGCAGUCUAAAUGCUCACCGAAGGGACUGUUAAUUUAUGAGACCAUGCGAUGAAGUACAACAGGACUUUAAAAAGACAGAGGUGGACCCACCUAUAUUCAUACAGAAAGAAAUCUAAGCCAUUAUAAGUGAACAAAAGCCAUUUGGCAAAUAUUUAUUGAGUGCCUGCUAGGUGCUAGGUAGUGUUCUCAGAGAUGGGGUCAGUGGCAGACUGGUGAACAGCUAAUCUUUUAGUCUAUUUGUGAUCAGUAUACAGUUGCAAAUUGGCAGGAAAAGGCCUAGAAGGAUCUAAAUCAUUAACAGAAGUUACCCUGGGGAGACCGGACAAAGGUGUUUUCUUUUAUAUACUCUUCUCUUGUUUGGAUUUUUUUUGCAAUGAGCAUAUGACUUUUAAAAUUUUGUUUUCUUUUUUUUUAAUUUGAGACAGGGUCUCACUCUGUUACCCAGACUGGAGUGCAGGAGGGAUCUUGGCCCACCGCAACCUCCACCCCUGCACGGGGGGCUCAAGCAAUCCUCCCAUGUCAGCCUCCUGAGUAGCUGGGACCACAGACGUGCACCACCACAACCGGCUACUUUUUUGUAGUUUCAGUAGAGACAGGGGUUGACCAGGCUGGUCUUGAACUCCUGAGCUCAAGAGAUCCACCCACCUCAGCUUCCCAAAGUGCUGGGAUUACAGCCCUGAGCCACCACACCUGGCUUACUGCAACCUCCGCUUCUUGGGUUCAAGCGAUUCUCCUGCCUCAGCCUCCCGAGUAGCUGGGAUUACAGGCAAGCGCCACCACACCUGGCUAAUUUUUGUAUUUUUAGUAGAGACGGGGUUUCACCAUGUUGGACAGGCUGGUCGCGAACUCCUGACCUCAAGUGAUCUGCCUGCCUUGGCCUCCCAAAGUGCUGGGAUUGCAGGCGUGAGCCACUGCACCUGGCCCAACUUUUGCAAUUUUUAAAAAGUGCUUCCUCCAUACAAACAGUAUUUACAUGUAGACGUAAUAAGGAGCCCUCAGGAUGCAAAAAGGGUUGGGGGUGGGGGUGUCUAAGCACAGUUUUCCAGAAUGUAGCCUCAGAAUCCUGGAUGGCCUCCCUUUGUUUCUCCCUACUCUGGGUACUCAGCUUUUCAAUGCAAGGCAGCAUUGAAAGAGCAAUUGAGGCAAGGGACCUGUUCUUCAGUCCCAGCUGAGCUACUCCUGGGCUGUGUGGCCUUGGGCAGGUCCCUCUACCUCUCUGAGCCUAAGCUUCCUUCCCCGUAUAAUGAAGGAAUAAGACUACACUUACCCAUGAAGGUAAGCAGAUUUUCUCACGCACAACACUGGCUAAUUGGGUGUGGCUACCUGCGGAAGUGGUGAGUGGGGACUGUAGGCUAUAGUGCUACUCAGCCUCAUGACCCAUUAGCAAUGUCAGUUGUGGACACAGGAUGGGGAAUAAGUGGCCUAUGUGAUGGAUUACUUAUGGGCUUGGACUAGAAGAUCUUAUCAUCGUCUGAUGAAUUGUUUGUUUGUUUGUUUGUUUUGAGUCGGAGUCUCUCUCAGUCGCCCAGGCUGGAGUGCAGUGGUACGAUCUCGGCUAACUGCAACCUCCGUCUCCUGGGUUCAAGCAAUUCUCUGCCUCAGCCUCCUGAGUAGCUGGGAUUACAGGCAUGCGCCACCACGCCAGGCUAAUUUUUGUGUUUUUAGUAGAGACAGGAUUUUGCCAUGUUGGCCAGGAUGGUCUUGAACUCCUGACCUCGUGACCCACCCACCUUGGCCUCCCAAAGUGCUAGGAUUACAGGUGUAAGCCACAGCACCCAGCCUUUGUUUGUUUGUUGUAUGGAUAAAAUUAACUUAUUAGGACAAUGGUAUUAUCGUAGAGGAAGAGUUUAAUAAAUGUAGGGCUAGUCAAGUGGGAAGAUGGGGGUUUAUUAUUUAAAUUUAUGUCUCUGAAAGUUUGGAAGGUAGCAUUUUUUAAGGAUAGUUUGGCGGGCAGGGGGCUAGGGAGAGGGAAAUGUUGAUUGGUUGGAUUGGGGAUGAAAUUAUAGGAAGUCGAAGCUGGCUUUUUUAUACUGAGGCAGUUUCGGGGUGGGGGUUAUAGGACUGGUUGAAUUAGUUUUUUGCUAUGAGUCACAGGUCUGGGUAGAAUCGUCAGAAUGUAAAAGUUCAAAAAAUAUUUUAAAGGCCAAUUUUAGGUUUUGACAGUAGUGAUGUUAUCUAUAGGAGUCGCUGGGGAGGUUACAAGUUCUGUAACCUCUGGCUAUAUUUCUCUGGAGUCAUAAUUUUAUAAAGGCAGUUUUGGUCACUGAGUAAAGAGGGGGUUAGUUUCAAGAAAGGACUGUUAAUUAUUUUUGUCUUAAACUAUUAACUCAAUUUUUGAAUAGUUAGUUUGGUCUAUGUCCAGGCAUGAGUGAAGACAGUUAGCUUGUGAGGUUAGAAGUAAGAUGGAGUCAGUUAUAUCGAUUUUUUUUACUGUUAAAUAUUUUUAUGUCAGAUUUUUUUCACUGUCAUAAGUUUUAUAAAAGCGGUUUUAAUCUCCAAGCUCCACUCCAGCUGUGACCUUCUCAGGAUUGAAAUAUUCUCACUUGCACCACAGUUGAGGUUGUCUAUGGCUGUGUGGCACAUUUGCAAUAGAAACCUGAGAGCUCAUAUUAAAUAUGGGUUAUUGAGCUGGGCUUGGUGGCUCCUGUCUGUGAUUGCAACACUUUGGGAGGUUGAGACAGGAGGAUUGCUUGAGUCCAGGAGUUCAAGAGCAGCCUGGGCAACAUAGCGAGACCACAUCUCUACAAAAAAUAAAAUUAGCCAGCAUGAUGGUAUGCACCUGUGGUCCCAGUUACUUGGGAGGCUGAGGUGGGAGGAUCACUUUAGCCCAGGAGGUUGAGGCUGCAAUGAGCUGUGAUUGUGCCACUGCACUCCAGCUUGGAUUACAGAGUGAGACUCUGUCUCGAAACGAAACAAAACAAAACAAAACAAAAAAUAUUUAUAUAUACACACAUACAGGUUACUAGAGCCAGCUCCUACUGGCUCAUGAGAGCUCAGGAACUUUGCAGUCAUGGUGGGGGUAUUUACACAGUGGAAACUGACUAAUAGUACAAACUGAGGUUGGUUGGUUGGUUUGUCCUAAAGAGCUGGUUUGCUACUAUAUCCUGACUAUUGUACUAAUAUGAAAUGCCCCUUUUUCCUUCUCACCCCAAUUUAGGGUGAUCAGCCAUCUCAAUUUGCCUGAAACUGCCCGGUAUUAGCACUGAAAGUUCCACAUCCCAGGAAACCUCUCAGACAUAGGCAAACUGGGAUGACUGGUCACCCUACAGUCUUUUCCCAUGAAGUGAAAGGAGCCAACCUUUGUUGAGAGCCCGAGAUCUCUGCUAGAUAAACCAUGUAAUACAGCAACCUUGCAAAGGAAACUUGCUAUGCUCACUUUACUGAGAGGAGACAGACUCAAAGAGACCUUAUUCAAAGCCUGUGCUUAUUAAUGCAUUUGACAGUAUCUGUUGAAUGUCUUCCAUGUGUGAGUCCCUGCAUGGAGUGCUGGGGAUGCUGUGGUGGGCGAGUCAGACCUGUCCCUGCCCCCAAGUGCAUGUAUCUUAACAGCAGAGACCGGCAUCUAACAAUUACUUAAAUACAAAAUGUGAUACAUAUUUUGAAGGAAAAAUAGAAGAAUUUAUGAACUGAUAACAGGGAAACCUGGUCUGGUCUGAUAAUCAGAGAAGGCGUCCUUGAGGAAGUGAUGUUUGAGCUGAGAUAUGCAGGAUGAAUAGAGGUAAACUGGGUGACAGGGGAGGCCGCACAGGCAGGCAGAAGGGACAGCAAAUGCAAAGGCUUGGAGGUGGGACCUGAGCAUGCUGUGUUCCAGAAAAGGCUGGAGCACAGACUCAGAGAGAGAGAGUGGGGUGGACGAGGCUGGAGAGAUUGGCAAAGCCCAGAUCAUGAGGGUUUUGUGGGUCACAGUGAGGAGCUUGAACUUCAUCCUUCUAGUAGAUUCUAGGCUACCCCUUCAGACACUCCUUAGGACCAGGGACACAUUCCCCGAGCUGCCAGGAGUGUUAGCAGCUGACAGAUCCUGGCUGGGUAUUUCUCUCCAACAAAGGGAGCUGCCUCCUUCACAUCUAAUGACUGUAAUGACCUGGCCCCCUUGCUUUGAUUUUGGGCAACGCUGAAGGGCUAUACCAGCUUAAAUCCCCCUGGGAUCAGUUGAAUAUUCUGUUGCAGAUGUUCAGCUUCCUCCACUGCCAAAUCCUGCUUCCUUCCUUACACGUGCUCUUCCUGAGAGCACUCCCCGCUAAAUCUCCCACACAUCAUCUCAGCUUCAGAAUCUUUUCCCUAGGGAUCCUGACCUGAGACACUCCUCAAGGCACUGGGAAGUUACUGCAGGGUUUUGAGAUGGGGAGUAACCUGCUGAGAGUUGCAUCUUAUGAAGAAGAUGAGUGGCAGCAGCAAAGGGUCAACUGAAGUGGGGGGCAGGGAGGAUACUACUGUCAUCAUCGAGGGAGAAAAGGAUGUGGCUUGGACUAGACAGAUAGGGUGGAGACCAAGAGAAUUAAGGAGUAUCGCAGUGCGUCAUCAUGAGAGUCAUUUAAAUUCUUAGUUUCAGUUUUUCCAAUUGUAACAUCGAAAUGAUGAUGCCUGUAUCUGUUAGGAUACUUUCUUAUCUAUUCAUUUUAACAAUAUAUUGAGCAAAAUUAAAGAGAUAUUCAGAGUCA